GAGCCCGGGAGCACUUCCGCCCUGUUGUGAAGUGGGUGUCUCGGUGGAGCCUUGGGGAGCAGUCCCUUUUCUAGGAGCCUCUUGAAGGACUCACCGUAGAUGCAGGAAGACAUUGGAUGAGGUCAGCAUAGCUGAAGUGAGGUGUCUGGGUUAGACAAUGGCUAUGGCCCUGGAAUUGCAAGCCCAGGCAUCUCCGCAGCCAGAGCCUGAAGAACUCCUGAUUGUGAAACUGGAAGAGGACUCUUGGGGAUCAGAAUCCAAACUCUGGGAGAAGGACCGUGGCUCUGUCUCUGGCCCAGAGGCCUCCCGCCAGCGCUUCAGGCAAUUCCAAUACAGGGAUGCAGCUGGACCCCACGAGGCCUUCAGCCAGCUCUGGGCUCUCUGCUGUCGUUGGCUGAGGCCGGAGAUCCGUCUCAAAGAGCAGAUCCUGGAGCUGCUCGUGCUGGAGCAGUUCCUGACUAUCUUGCCUAGGGAGGUCCAGACCUGGGUGCAGGCACGCCACCCUGAGAGUGGUGAGGAGGCUGUGGCCUUGGUGGAGGAUUGGCACCGAGAGACCAGGACUGCAGGACAGUCGGGACUGGAAUUGCAUACAGAAGAGACCAGGCCCUUAAAGACAGGGGAAGAAGCUCAGAGCUUCCAGCUGCAGCCAGUGGAUCCCUGGCCUGAGGGACAGUCCCAGAAGAAGGGGGUGAAGAAUACAUGCCCUGACCUUCCCAAUCACCUAAAUGCCGAGGUGGCACCACAGCCUUUGAAAGAGAGUGCUGUCCUCACUCCCCGAGUCCCUACUCUCCCAAAGAUGGGGAGCGUUGGAGAUUGGGAGGUGACAGCUGAGUCCCAGGAAGCCCUGGGCCCUGGCAAACAUGCUGAGAAGGAGCUCUGUAAAGACCCCCCAGGAGACGACUGUGGGAACAGCGUGUGCCUGGGAGUUCCAGUUUCAAAACCAAGUAAUACCUCCGAGAAAGAGCAAGGACCAGAGUUUUGGGGUCUAAGUCUUAUAAAUUCUGGGAAAAGGAGCACUGCAGAUUACAGCCUGGAUAAUGAGCCAGCUCAGGCAUUGACCUGGAGGGAUUCAAGAGCCUGGGAGGAACAAUACCAGUGGGAUGUGGAGGACAUGAAGGUGUCAGGUGUUCACUGGGGCUAUGAGGAGACCAAGACUUUCCUGGCAAUUUUGAGUGAAUCUCCUUUCUCUGAAAAGCUCCGGACUUGUCACCAGAACCGCCAGGUAUAUCGGGCCAUUGCAGAGCAGCUAAGGGCAAGGGGCUUCCUGCGGACACUGGAGCAAUGUCGCUAUAGGGUCAAAAACCUCCUACGGAAUUACCGGAAAGCCAAGAGCAGCCACCCACCAGGUACCUGCCCCUUCUAUGAGGAGCUGGAGGCCCUGGUCAGGGCUCGGACAGCCAUCAGAGCCACAGAUGGCCCAGGAGAGGCCGUGGCACUUCCCAGGCUCGGGUAUAGUGACGCAGAGAUGGAUGAGCAGGAGGAAGGGGGCUGGGAUCCUGAAGAAAUGGCAGAAGACUGUAACGGUGCUGGCCUGGUCAAUGUUGAGUCUACCCAGGGGCCCAGGAUUGCAGGGGCCCCAGCUCUGUUCCAGAGUCGUAUUGCAGGUGUGCACUGGGGCUAUGAGGAGACCAAGGCCUUCCUGGCAAUUCUCAGUGAGUCCCCAUUCUCGGAAAAGCUUCGUACCUGUCACCAGAACAGCCAGGUGUACCGGGCCAUUGCAGAGCGGCUGUGUGCUCUGGGCUUCCUGCGGACACUGGAGCAGUGUCGCUACAGAUUCAAAAACCUCCUUCGAAGCUACCGGAAAGCCAAGAGCAGCCACCCACCAGGGACAUGCCCUUUCUAUGAGGAACUGGACUCGCUGAUGAGGGCUCGGGCUGCAGUCAGGGCCAUGGGGACUGUCCGAGAGGCUGCAGGUCUCCCUAGGUGUGGGCAGAGUAGUGCUGAGACUGAUGCCCAGGAGGCCUGGGGUGAAGUGGCCAAUGAAGAUGCUGUCAAACCUUCAACCUUGUGUCCUAAAGCCCCAGACAUGGGUUUUGAAAUGAGGCAUGAGGAUGAAGACCAGAUUUCAGAGCAGGACAUUUUUGAGGGUUUGCCUGGAGCCUUAUCAAAAUGUCCUACAGAAGCUGUUUGCCAACCUCUUGACUGGGGAGAAGACAGUGAAAAUGAAAAUGAAGAUGAAGGGCAGUGGGGAAAUCCCUCACAGGAACAGUGGCAAGAAAGUUCUUCUGAAGAGGACUUAGAAAAACUUAUUGACCAUCAAGGCCUGUACCUUGCAGAGAAACCCUACAAGUGUGACACAUGCAUGAAGAGCUUCAGUCGGAGCUCCCACUUCAUUGCCCAUCAGCGAAUCCACACAGGUGAGAAGCCCUACAAAUGCCUUGAAUGUGGAAAAAACUUUAGUGACCGCUCUAACCUCAAUACCCAUCAGAGAAUCCACACUGGAGAGAAGCCCUAUAAAUGCCUUGAAUGUGGGAAAAGCUUUAGUGACCAUUCUAAUCUCAUCACUCACCAGAGAAUUCACACGGGGGAAAAGCCCUAUAAAUGUGGAGAAUGUUGGAAAAGCUUCAACCAGAGCUCAAACCUUCUGAAACAUCAGAGAAUCCACUUGGGAGGAAAUCCUGACCAGUGUAGUGAGCCUGGGGGAAACUUUGCCCAAAGCCCAUCUUUUAGUGCUCACUGGAGGAAUUCUACAGAAGAGACAGCUCCUGAACAACCUCAAAGUAUCAGUAAGGACUUGAAUUCUCCUGGACCACACAGCACAAACUCAGGGGAGAAACUUUAUGAGUGUUCUGAAUGUGGAAGAAGCUUCUCUAAGAGCUCUGCCCUCAUUAGUCACCAAAGAAUCCAUACGGGAGAGAAACCAUAUGAAUGUGCCGAAUGUGGGAAAAGCUUCAGUAAGAGCUCCACCCUGGCCAACCACCAGCGCACCCACACUGGAGAGAAGCCGUAUAAAUGUGUGGACUGUGGGAAGUGCUUCAGUGAGCGCUCCAAGCUCAUCACACACCAGAGAGUGCACACAGGAGAGAAGCCCUACAAAUGCCUUGAGUGUGGAAAAUUCUUCCGUGACCGUUCUAACCUCAUUACUCACCAGAGGAUUCAUACGGGAGAGAAGCCGUAUAAGUGCAGAGAGUGUGGGAAAUGCUUUAACCAGAGCUCCAGUCUUAUUAUUCACCAGAGAAUCCACACAGGGGAGAAACCCUACAAGUGCACAGAGUGUGGCAAAGACUUCAACAACAGUUCCCACUUCAGUGCUCACCGGAGAACCCAUGCAGGAGGGAAGGCGUCGUAGGGGACAGUUUCCUCAACAACAAAGGAGGACUCAAUGUAUAUAUCUUAUAUCAUAAGAUGUAUGCUAGAGAUAAACUUUCCAAUUUUUAAGCUUGGUGUGUACCCAGGGAAGUUAUCUUGGUAUAAACCAGGUAAUUUGGAAGUGAAUUACAAAUACUAAGGAUCCAGAUUUGAAGGCACUUUUAAGUGUAAUUUGUUUUUCUUCUGUAAAGACCCACACAGAAUCCUGACUGUCCUUGUAUUUGCUAUCAUGUAAGAGCUGUGUCAGUAUUUGAGCCAAACUGGCAACUUACGAGAUUAGAGUUAAAUCAGUGGUCCUGAGCAGUGAUUCCAAACUCUCACUGUGCCUUCACACCAUCCAUGUGUAAUCCACCCCAUCAGCAGUGGUUCUCCUACUUUCUCAGUGGGGGCAUAUCCUCAAGGGAGAAUGUUGUGACUCUGGUGAGAGAGGAGUUGGCCUAGAGCAGGCCACUGUGAGCUCAGCACAGAGUAGGAAGAACAGUGACAUCAUUACAAAAUCAUCAAUAGCAGCAAUAGCUGGUGUUUAUUGAGCUGUUGCUCUUUGGCAAGCUCUGUGCUAAGAACUUUGUAUACAUCAUCUCAUUUAAUCUUCACAACGGCCCCAGGAGAUAAGUACUAACUUUCUCCCCAUUUCCUAGAGGCUUGGGAAAUUAAGUAACUCGCACUGGUCACACAUCUGUAAGUGGGAGAGGCAGGAUUCAACAGAUCUGUCUGUCUUGAGUCUAUCGUGCUCUUAUUGCUAUACUGAAUUCCCAUUCAUGUUAGGUAACUUAGGGGCCAGAAUCUCCAUGCACUUUGUAGACCACAUUUCCUGUUAUGAAAUUUCCACAUUUUGAAUUUUUUAAACAAAUAUGGAAACUGAGAAUCCCUAAGGAUUAAAGGACUUGGGAUAUCCAGAAUUGGUGAAGUGAUUUGAGCAAGGAUGAGCUAUUAUCAAAAUACUUGAUGUGAGUUUCCAUCUUCGCAAUAAUAUGGGUGAGAGAUAUAGGUGGGUUGAGAUUGGGAAAAAUAUGCGGCCUAAGUAAUUUUUCUUCCAAUAAGAUACUGCUUUGGCUAAGGAAAUGGGAUGUAAGAGUUCUCUUUUUCUCAGGGGACAGUCCUACUUCUUGCCAUGCUUGGCUGAUCAUAGGUUAACCCUAACAGAAGCCUGGGGUCCCUACAUUUUUGUCUGUCUGGCUUUUCCUUUUGGCAAGCAGAAGCUUUGUUCUUGGUCCCCAUGCCAAGACUGAGGUGGGAGGUGCUGGUGUAUAUGGUCAUCUACUGAGAGGGCCUUGACCACUGUUCUGUGUACCAGGUUCUUGGCACAAUUUUACCCUGAGCCAUCCUGUCCCAGGCCUGCCCAGGGCUUUCUGUAUGUUGACCCUUAAGACUCACCUCCCACAUGGACAGGCUAAGUUAGAAAGGUUCACAUAGGAUGGUUUUAACAUUUGCAGCACUUUGGCCUCCAGAGUUUCUCCUUAGAAGGGUUUAAAACUGUUGACCAAGGACUUCGGUUUCCAUAGGACUUUAAAGGAAAAUCCCCCUCCUGCCAUCCUCUUAUGACACUAGGAUGUAUUCAUAACCUGCUUGGUUCAUGGGCUGGGGAAGUACCUAUCAGAUAGUGGAUGUGAAGCAGCCUUGAAGAAUGGAACUUUUAUUAACAUGUGAGGAAGCCAGUGGAGAGAUUUGCUACUCCCACAGAGUGAUAUCCCUUCUUAACCCCUUCCCCUGCUUCAGAACCUCCUUUCCCAAGAACCAGCCCCACUAGGAUCACCGUCAACUCCCUCCCAGUUUACCUUUUCUGGCCCACGUUAUCUCUGCGGGGCAGGGGUCAUGGGAUGAACCCUGGAUAGAAGUCAGCAGAUGUCAGUAACUGCAGUAAUACAGUGAUAUUGUCUAGUAAUGUGAGCUGAGAGGAAGGAUCCUGAGGUGAGGGAGAGGGAGGGAAUUCCAGGGAAAGGCACUGUUGUGUGGAAUAGCAUGGAUUCAGGGUGGGGUUGUAUGAUGGGAGGUUGGGAACAGGGAGCUGAUAUUAGAGGAGUGCUGGAGCAAGGUCACUGAGGACCUCACAUGUGAAUGGAGUGUCAACACCAGGCCCGGGGCAAUGUUCAGAUGUGCAUGGUUGAAAUCUGACAGCUGAAUGGAACUUGGACAUGCUGCAAUUAGGAUGGCCUUUUGGGACACUGUUGUGGUAUUUCAGCUAAAGGCUAGGGUCUGAACUAGAGCAGUGGUGACACUGAGGAGGAGGGAAUGAAUGGGAAAGGUCUCAGAGGCAGAGGGGAGGACAUCAGAGGAAAGCUAGAAUGCCUUUGGUGACUGGGUAGAGCAUGUCCUCAUUCAGAAUUGGGAGCACAAGGAGGAGAGGCUGAUAGAGCAGGAGGGCAGAAGAUGAGAAGUUUAGUUUGGUAUGUCUAGAACUUGAGGUGCUUAAGGGAAAUCAUGGUGAUGCUAUGCAUUUGGAUGUCGGCUAGCAGCUAGGGGAGAGGCUAGGACUAGAGAUCUGUGUAUGCGAAGUAGUUAAACUAAUGAGAAAGGAAGAAUUUCAGUUUCAAAUAUUGGGCCUAGGACAGAGCUACUUGAUAGUGCUGAAUGGAGAGGAAGAUGGCCCUCAAAGGAGAUCUAGACCAUUCCCCACUCCCACCCACUACCAUCAUGUUCUGGACCCUGUCUUCUUUGUUACUGACCCCUGAAUUCUUCAUGUAGCCCUGAGUUUUCUGGAGCCCUCACUGUGGAAGUCAAGCUGAGCUCUGUGUGGAUGUGAGGUGGUAGUCCUCUCUCCACUUGGUCACCCUUUCCCCUGGGUUUGGUAGUGUGUUAGUGUCUCAUAUCUUUAGUGAACAGUUUUGAUGUUUAUUAUCUGCCAUUCUUGUCUCAUGAAUCUUAAUAGAGGUUCAGUCAUGAAAGCAAGGCCAGUGUGGGCCAGGUGAGAAAAUGGCCCAGGUGGUCCCUUCCUCCUUGUCUACCUGACUUCCUUUGGAAGAAGCACUCUUUCAGGGGGCUUCAGUGUUCCAGGCUUGCUGUCUACCCAAGAGCUUGCUGGGCACCCAGGCGCCCUCCAGUAGGUCUGUGCUGCUCAGAUAAACUGACAUCUGGUUUUACACACCCUGAGCUUUGCUAGCGUGAUUCUGCUCUUGGGAAGUAGAUUCACUCUGCAGAAUGGGUGGACAGUUUCUCAGCCUUCCUGGCCACAGGUCAGACCCUGGUUAUGGAAAACCAAACCAGCAAAUGCUGCCCUGGGAGGGUGUUACAUCAUGUGAGCUGCUAAAGGCAGGAUCGUCUCCCCAGAUGGCUGCCUCCCCUUGAUUUCUUCACCCUCCACCUCAAGAAGGGCAUUGGCUCCUCUGAAGGGACAAAAAGGUACCUAAAGGACCUUAGGCCUCCCAUUCCUCAGACCCCCAGAGGCAGCAGACCCAAAGGUAGGGGCAGGGAAAGGAGGGGCCAAGACUUUUUCAGAUACUCGGUUUUUUCUAAGGCCUUGACCUCAGCAGCUGAACUCAUGGUCAUGGCUGCCUUGGCCUUAUUGUCCACUGUAGCCUCCUCCCAGAAGCCGAGUAAAGCAGCUAGGGUCCCUCCAUGCUAAAUAAUGUAGUCAGGCGCUCUGGGUAGUCCGUCCUGCCUCAUCUUGUUCUGGGGCCCCCAGUGGGGAUAGCUCUCUGCUUUCGGGCUGCAGAAAAGAAUUGAGUCACUUUCUGUAGGGGAGUAACACCCUUUGGGGACAGGGGUGCAGUUUUGAAGUAAUGAAGGCAGUGAUGUCUGGAGUGGGUGUGGGUGUUGCAGGUGAACUUGCCUCACCCAGGCUGUUCUGGGUCUUUGUACUCCAGAGUUCUGUCCUAGGCUUGCUUCUUCAUUCACUCUGUUUCCCUUUCUCUUCUUUUUUUCUUUUCCUUUCUUUCUCUCUUUUCUUCUGUGUAGAUGCUAAUGACUUCCAGAUCUGUGUCCUGCUGUGGCCUCUCCUCUUAGGAUCCCAGCUGCCUGCCAACCAGCUGUGCUUGGGUGACUCCUGGGCAUCUCAAAGCCCCGGUGUCUACCAUCACCCAUCAUGGGGCUCUUGGCCUGCCCAUUCAGCACGUGCAUUGAUGUACACACUCAGUGACUCCCAUCCAAGCCUCCCCUGCACGUGCCUGGAGAGACCUGCCCAUUGGACUCAUCUUGGACUCAGUUCUGCCAAUACUUUCUCCCUUCUAAGAGCAUUUCCAGUUGGGCUGGAGUUACCCAGCUGCCUGAGAGGUCUCUUUCUGAAUGAAGUCAAUAUCUAAAGUCAAAAUUAAUCAUUCAAAAUAUUCCCUUACCCCAUUUUUUUUGGGGGGGAGAUGGGGGUCUUGUGUUGCCCAGGCUGGUCUUGAACUCCUGGCCUCAAGCGAUCCUCCCACCUCAGCCUCCCAAAGCUCCCCUUAACCUCAGUUUUGAUCCCAUCCUCCAUUUGGGCAUUGCUCAGCUCCCCCACCUGUUAAUAGCAAACACCAAUCUCAAGCCCCUGCCCCAAUCUGCUACAAGGGGUUAGUGUUCCAUGCAGUGGGAGUGCAGGGAAGGCUUUACAGGAGAGGAGGGAGUUGAAAUGGGCCUGGAGGCCUGGGAUGGUAGACACUGGAUCCUUUUCCCCCACAGCUCCUGGCUGUUUCUUCACACUCCCAGCAUCACUAUUACUGCUAGCAUGUCUUUAGCAUCAUUUUGCCCUCCCUCUGACUUUCAGCAAGCCUGCACUUACCUCCAAAUAAAUGCAUGUUUUCGGGGGGCAAAGGCAGGUUCCUUCCUUACCUUAUUGUUGCUUCCCCCACCCCAUGCUGCAGCUGAGUGGGUGACCUUUCUCCUCACCUCCGUGUGCCGCAUCUCUCACCUAGUCUCUGUUAGGAACCCUACAGGAGCCUGCACCCCAGUAACCCCAUUUUAUGCUGCUUGGAGGAAGAGACAGAGAGUUUGAGAGGUCCCAGUUCUUUUCAGUGUGUGUUUGGUUCCCCCACUUCUCAAAGCUGAGAGCUUCUUUGUUUUAAGAGCCACUUGGUUAAGUCAAGAGCAUUAGAAGAGUAAAAAGAAGAAUACAAUUAGAUAAUUUUACCUAAACAUGCUAUAGUCGACUAGGGAGUCACAUAGACAUUGAUUUUCUAAUGAGGGCGCUGUUGGUGAUUCUUUUUGUGUGUAAAGAUGCUUCUGAUCAUGCCUGCUAUUACAUGAUACUUAUUUCUAAAGUCACUUUUUUUUUUUUUUUUACAUUUUCAUUGUAGAAAAAUAUCCCAUAAAAAUUGUGCCCCCUAGAGGGCGAGGGCCACGGGAAGGGGGAUCAGGAAAACAAGAAUCAGUCUCUAAGCUGGUCCUGGAGCAGCAUGACAGAUGUAUCUGAGCCCAAGCAGGAGAGGAGCCACAGGCCCAGGCUGGCAGAGUUGUGACUACUAGAAUCUCGAGUCACUGGGGCUCAGGGAGCCCUAACUUGGUGGCAGGUGACAAAUGUGGCACAAAGGAGAAAGGAGUCUUCUCCUUCCACAUAGAACACACUUGGCUUCAGUGCUUUGGGGGGAUUCGUGGACCACAGAGAAGCUUCCGCAUAUUUAUAGGCACUGGGGACCAGCAGGAAGUGGUGGUGAGACACUUUGAAACCCUCCACUGCAGACUUCACCCAGGGGGCAAGGCAGGAGAGAAUCCCUCUGUGGACAGCACUUGAGAGGAAAGGGCUUGUUCAUGACCACGUAUGAGGUCGCCAACCCAACCCUGUUCCUGAAGUUUCCCAGAAAUAGAUGGAGAGGUAAGGCCAGCUAGGCUGGAGCGCCAGCAUCAGUAGUAGGGGCAGGAGCUCACGCUAAACCCGGUUGGUGUGUCCUGGAGAAGCACAGGUGUCAUCUCCAGGGACCUUUCUCGACCAACUAAUUUAUGGAAAUGAGACAUUUGUAAUUGAUUUUAAUUCCCUCUUAGGGACUGUGAAAUUAAAAUGGAUUAAAUUUUGUCCAUCAGGAGCCUCAGGGAUUUAAUGUCCAAUUCUAAAACCUGAACAGGCCCUUUUGUUUUGCAAUUUGUGGACCAAUCCCUGGCUUCAUUUUAUUUGGCUUUGCUUUCACUUCCCCAUUUUCUGUUAUUUUUUUUUUUUUUGUGCUGUUAUGUACAUCUCUUAAAGCUGGUCAAAUCAUAUUUUGGGAUGGAAUGGCCUGAUAAGUUAAUAAAUUAUAUUAAACUGCCAAAAAA